AACUGCUGCCAUUAUCUGUGCAAACUAUGGUUUGAGUACUUUUAAUUUAGCAAAGACUAAUUAUUUUUUAAAAAUUUUGGGGUAAAAAAAAUGGUCUUUAGCGUAGAAGAGCUUUACCCGACUUACUUUAGUUGGUUCAAUUGGUUGAUUUUGGUUUGCUUUUUGAAAUUUUGUAUUGUCUUAAUUUGGGGCACAUUGAACUCAAUAACAGUUCAGUUGCAUUAUAAUUCAUUUGGGUAAAGUUUAUUGUUGGAGGAGGGUAAGUAAAUAUUUAACUGAAAAAGUGAAGUAAAUAUUUAUUUAAGGCUAUAAGUUGAAAUAUUUGUCAGCUGAGAAAUUUUCAGGUAACUUUUUUAACCUUUGAAAAAAAUUUACUAUAGCAUGAGUAUUUUUUAUACUGCUAUGUAUAAUCCAUAGUCACGUUUUUUAACCUUUUUAUAUAAAAUACUGAUACAGAAAACCAUACAAUCAUAGUAAUCUUUUAAAAUUGCUUUAUAAUUCACAUAGCGUAACAUUCACCCAUUUAAAGUUUACAGUUCAGUAGUCUUUAGUAUAUUCAGACUUAUGCAACGAUUAACACAAUUUAAUUUUAGAACAUUUUCAUCACCUCCAAAAGAUACCCUGUACUCAUUAGCAGUCACUCCCCAUUCACCAGUCUCCCAGCCCUUAUCAACCAUUAAUCCAUUUUCUGUCUAUAGAUUUGUCUAGUUUAGGUAUUUUAUAUAAAUGGAAUACAGGUAACUUUUUAUUAGUGAUUUUUCACUUACAUGUGUCUUGCAUGUCUCAUGAGAUAGCUAUGAAUAAGUUAGCCUUCUUUUACAACUUAAAUAACAAUUCUUGUCUGACCGGGAAAAAGUAUUAAGUUAUUGAGAGACUGCAUCCCAAUUUAAACCAAGAACCAGACUCCUUACUAGUAUUAUAACUCAAAAGAAUGUGUACCAUUAGCCCUUACCUCUGGUGGUGCUUUUCACUGUGAAUUGUUCAGCAGCCUCUCAACUUCCCGAAAAUACCACUUAAGUCUUAAACUCAGACUUGCAUGAGUUUACUGAGAUAUGUUUACCUUUGCAGCUGGCUUGCCUAGAGUCUACCUUCUUACUACCCUACUAAGUCCAGAAUGAGGAAGAAUUAAAAGCAAGAAAGGAGAUACAGAAGAAGAGAUUGCUCAGGCUGAGGAGGGGCAAAGUGAUAAGAGCAGGAUUAGAAAGAGACAUUAAAAAUUCAAGGAUACUGAGUUUGUUGGCAUCAGAAUAAAUCUUGGAGGCUGUUUUAAGAGGGAAUAAAACCUAGAGGGAAGGAAUAAAAGGCAAAGAUGUUAUAAAACAUAGGUAAAAUAUUUAAAAUAUUUUGUCCUGAAUUUUGAAUUUUAGGCAUAUGUCAGUGAAGCACAAAGGAUAGCCCCCUUUUUUGAUGAGCUUUAGUAUCCUUAAGAUAUUUUCUUUCUAGAACCUUGUGUAGGAAUUUUACAGCUGACCAUAAUCAUGUGUUCUCUUUGGUUUGUUCCAACAUCUUUGGAUUGGAACCAGUACAGAGUAGGAAACCCAUAUCACCUUGGGAUUAUUUUUCAGAUAAAUCUUCCAGAGGAUUAAAUGGCACCAUCCCCGUCAGGUCCAAGUAGGAGGGGAAGAAUCCUAUUUUGGGUGCUGUCAGAUUCAGUGGGCUGUUUAGUUCACUUUUUAUCCAGAAAAUGGAGCUAAAUGAGAAAUUGCAGCUUCCAAAGAAAAUCAUACCUUGAUUUUAUAGAUCAAAGCCUUUCUGAUUAGAUCAGAAUUGUUCCUGAGAUUUUAGGGGCAUUCAGUUAAAGUGCCCCAAGAAGAGUGAUAAAUCACAUAUAGGUGUAAAGUCAAUAAAGUCCUAUAGUAAGCAGACUGGAAUUUAGGGGGAGGGGAAUACACACUGUUAGACUGUUGGUACCUAUAUUUGACUACUAGGAUGAUUAUAUAUUUUAAAUUCUGUAUUCAGUUUCUUAUCAGAAAUACUGCCUACAAUAUCUUAUACUUAAUUUUUUAAGGAACAGGUGAUAAAGAUAGGUUAUAUUUUCUUCAGAAUAAUUGAUAUUCAUUAUUUAAUAGAUAAAAUGUGUUAUCUGAAUGUUUAUAGUAGUAGAAACCAAGUUUACAAAAUGUCUAUAUAUAAUUUGUUUUUAAUAACCAAGGAUUCUUUCUUUACAAAAGAUUUCCUCUAUAUAAAUCUUCCUGUUUUAUAGAUGAUCUGUAUUAUAGGAGAAAUGAGUAUUUGUUGAUUUAACUGGCUAAUCUACAGGACUGAGCAUUAUUAGAGGAGUAUUUAAACAUAGAAGUCUGUGAAAAUAUUUUUAGUGCUGAGGGAAAUUGGAGGGACUUUCUAGAACCGCAAACUAAUAGAAAACCAGGCAUAGUGGCUCAAGCCUGUAAUCCCAGCAUUUUGGGAAGCCGAGGCGGGAGGAUUGCUGAAGCCCUGGAGUUUGAGACCAGCCAGGGCAACACAGUGAUACCUUGUCUCUACAAAAAAAUUUUUAAAAUUAGCUGGACGUGGUGGCACAUCUAUACUCCCAGCUACUUGGGAGGCUGAGACGAGAGGAUCACCUGAGCCCAGGAGCUCCACGCUAUAGUUUGAGUUGUGAUCGUGCCAUUGCACUAUAGCCUGGGUGACAGAGCAACACCCUACCUCAAACAAACAAACAACAAAAAAACCCUUCUACCUCUGAACAUGUGGGGAUUUAAAGAUUGCUAUGAUUUAAAUAUAAAUCAUGAAUAUAGAAAAUAUGAGAACAGAAGAGUAUUUGUUAAACAAGACUAAGCUGUGCUGCAUAAAGUAAGGCACUAUCAUUGUGCUGGUAUUUUCUGAUUCUCUUAGUGCAAUAAAUGUUAAACUUUACUACUACCUUAGCCAUGUUGCAGGGAAUUGACAUGAAUAGUUCCUGGGUUUUGGCUGGGUGCGGUGGCUCACGCCUGUAAUCCUAGCACUUUGGGAGGCUUAGGUGGGCAGAUCAGGAGUUCAAGACCAGCCCGGCCAACAUGGCGAAACCCUAUCUCUAAUAAAAAACUUAAAAAUUAGCCGAACGUGGUGGUGCACGCCUGUAGUCCCAUCUACUCAGGAGGCCGAGGCAGGAGAAUUGCUUGAACCUGGGAGGUGGAGGUUGCAGUAAGCCAAGAUGGCACCACUGCUCCUAGCCUGGGUGACAGAGGGAGACUCCGUCUCAAAAAAAAAAGUUCCUGGGCUUCAAGGGCACUCUAAUGUGCACAUCUUAAAUUCUUAGAGCCUACUUCUAUGGACGAUUUAUGUUACUGUUGAUGGAGAAUUUGAUUUUCUUUUUUAUCUUCCCCUUUCCCUUGGCCUUUGUAGGUUUUUUGAAGUGAACAUACUUUUAUGUAUUUACUUAUUUAUUGAGCAGUUCCCAAAUGGCAACUUUAUUAUUUUAUUUCUUCAACUCAGUUGUCUAGUUUACUUCAUUUGUAUCUAAUCUAUUUAACUCAUCCUUUGAGUUUUUAAUAUCAACAUUUUAAAUUUUAUUUUUUUAGCUUCAAAGGUGUGCAUAUGCUUGUUACAUGGAUAUAGCAUGUAUAAUGGUGGAGGUUGGGCUUCUAGUGUACCCAUCACCCAAAUACUGAAGGUUGGACCCAAUAGGUAGUUUUUCAACCCUCACCCUCUCCCACCCAAUUGUUUUUAUUUCUGAAAGUAAUAUUUCUUUCUUGGUCUGCCUGAUAAUUUUUUUAUAGUUUCUUAUUUUUCGUUAGUUUUCAAAAAAUACCUUGUUGGGCAUUUUGUCCAUAGAUGUACUAUCUUAUGUUUGCUAAUUCCAAUAUCGGAAGUCCUUAGGAAGUUGUACUUAAGGUAGUUUGUUUCUUUCUGUAUUUGGUGAUUUUUUUUAUGAGCUAAUAUUUGAUUAAACCGAAUAUUUCUCCAUCCUCUGUAUAGUUGCCUACAAUGUAAUUUCUACUUUUUUUUUUUUAGCAUAAAAGAGUUUCAUUUUCCUUUUUAUACUCAAUAACUUGUUUAAUUAGCCAGUAUUUUUACCAGUUUCUUUACUUAUUGUUCCUUGCAUCUUCUCUGAGUCCACUUUUCUUCUUGCUGAAGUACAUCCUUUAGUAAUCCUUUUAGUAAGAGGCUGGCUUGUAAAUGUCCUUAGUUUUUGUGUGAAAGUAUAUUUUAUGCAUUACUUUGUUUUUCAGCUAGAUAGGGAAUUCUUGGUUGAUAGGUUUCCUCCCAUCAGCAACCUCAGUAUAUUAUUUCAUUGUCUUGUGAAACUUGGCAAACUUGGAUCUCUGAGAAGUUCGAUCUCUGCCUAAUUGUUAUGCUUCUGUAUGUAAUUUUUUUUUUCUGGUAGUUUUUUAAAAGAUUUCUUUUCUUUAUUCUGUCACCACUACUUACUGUGUGACCUUGGGCAAGUUCAAAAUGGAUAUAAAAUUGUAUCUGUGUCAUAGGGUUGUAAUGAGGAUUAAGUUUUAAAGCACUUAGAACAGAGCCUUGCAUAUUAUAACUGUGACAUGUUAAUAUUUGUUUUAUUUUGCCAUACUUGAUAUUCUAAACACAUUUCUAUGAUAUGCUUAAGUAUGUUGUUUUAUCCAUAGCUCCUCUUUGAAAUACAUUGUUGAUGGGAAGAUUCAUAUCUUUCUUUGUUUCUAGAAAAUUCCUUAGCCUUCAUAUCUUUGAAUAUUCAUUUUCCAAUAUUCCUUCUUAGUCUCUGUAUUAUGUUCUAGGUGGUUCCUCAGUAUCAUUUUCUAAUUUACUAAUUCACACUUUGACUUUGUCCAGCUAGAGUUUAUGUGGCCUCAGUUCCAGUGAAUUUUUUUUAAAUAUUCAGGCUGUCUCUCUAAUAGCCACCUAUUCUGGUUUGAUUUCUGCCUAUUUUUAAUUUUUCUUCCUUUAAUGACUAUUGUGGCUUCCUUUUAACAUUUGAAAUUAUUUUCAGAUUGUCAUUUUUUCUUCUAGAAUGAAUUACAGUUGUUGAUUUUAUUGGCUGUCCAUCUUAGUUUAGUUUUCUUUGUGUGUUUUGAGUUUGCUUUUGCAGUCUCCUAUUGACUGGAAGUUUUUGUUGUGUUUUCUUUUUCACUCUUCUUAUCCAGUGUUUUUACAUGCACCUACAUCUCUGUCUAAAACCACAUCUUUAUAUUGGAGGCUUGAUUCCCUUGAUUCUUGGUAACAUCAGGAUCAGGCUUCUCUUUCCAAGAAUAAGACACAAACUAAGAUCUAUAUUUCUUCUCACUGGACACAUAAUUUCAUCUAAACCGUAGCCCCAUGCAAUGGUUAGUAGUAGCUUUUUCUGGCUCCUUUCAUUGGUUGGAAGAGCCUCUCCACCCUAGGUAUUGGUUUCAAGCAGUGAGCCUGAGUUCUAUCCCAGCCAUGCAUGGGUACCUUUUUAGUCCCUGUUACUAUCCCUACAGGAUGUGGACUUUUGGCCAUCUCUGUUACUUGAGCCCAGAAGGCUCACAGUUUUAGCUUCAAAAACUGCUUUGUAUUUAAAGAGUUCAGUGGCUUGGUCUUUUUUAAUAUUUUGUUUGUAUAGUUAAUAAAUAUUUAACAUACAUUAAAAUGUUUGGAACAGAUACAUUUCAAAAGUGAAUAUACAAAUCCAUUUGGUUGGAAGUUAGUCCAUUUUGUGUUGCUAUCACAGAAUAUCACAGACUGGGUAAUUUAUUAAUAAUAGAAGUUUAUAUAGCUCUUGGUUCUGAGGGUGGUAAGUCUAAGAUUGAGGGGCUGCGUCUGGUGAGGGCCUUCUUGCCAGAUGGAAGGCAGGAAUGCAAGAGAGCACAAGUGCAAACAAGGGCAAGACGGGGCCAGACUCGAUUUUACCAGGAACUCACUCCUAAGAUAAGGGCAUUACUCAAUUCAUGAGGGCAGAGCCUUCAUCACCCAGUUACUUUUUAUGGACUCACUGGUUAUUACUGUCACAAUGACAAUUCAAUUUCAACAUGAGUUUUGGAGGUGACAUUCAAAUCAUAGCAGAAGUCAAUGUUUAAAAUCAAUGUAUAUCCUACAUACCCUUCAGAAAGAUACUAGUUGACUCUCCUACUUAUGAGAGGUAUAUUUUUUUAUUCCUUUGCCAAUAUUGGGUGUAAUAAUUUUUUAAUCUUUGAGAAGGUAAUGUAUAAAAAACAAAUUUGUGUUUAAUAGCUAGCAGGAUUGGUCAUUGCUCCAUAUAUUUAUUACCCAUUUAUAUUCUUUUAUUUAUUUAAUUGCCUGUUCACAUUCAUUGCCCAUUUCUUUUCCUUUAAGGUGUUCAUUUUUAUUGUCUUUUAAAAUAGCUGUUUGUAUAUUGUAGUAAUGUUAACUUUUGUGUAUAUAUUGCAGAUGCUUAAAAGACGUUUGCUUUUCAGGUUAAUGAGCUUUAUUUUAUAGUGUAGGAGUUUCUUUUCUCUGGAGUCACUUUUUCUUAUUCCUUUGGAAUCAGUCUUUUCUUGUCAUCCUUAGAAAGUCCUUUCCUACCAUAAGAUUACAGAAAUAUUUGCAUACAUCUACUGGUAUUGUUUUAUUAUUAAUACUUCAGACUUCAAUCUUUAAUCUCUUGGUAUUUAUUUUAAGGUGUGAUGUUGAAGGGAUUCAGCUACCCACCACUGGAGGGCAGGAGUGGAAAAGAUCAGCUUUCAGGCACCCAUUAUUGAAUCUCUCUGUUCCCAGAGAGCUCUUUCUGGAUUCUCAGUUCUAUUCCACUGAUAAAUUUAUUCCUGCAUUAGUAUUGCCUCUUAAAUACUAUAAUUUGGAAUCAAGUUUAAAUAUCAGGUAUUGCAGAUUCUCAUGAUUUUAAGAAUGUUUUGGCUAUUCACAUUUAUUCAUAUAUAUUUUGAAAUGAUUUAAUCAAGGUCUGGGAACAAAAAGGUCCAGUUGUGAUUAUAUUGAAUUUAUAGAUUAAAUAAAGGGAGGAUAACCAUCUUCACAAUUUUGAAUCUUCCUAUCCAAGAAAAAGAAGUGUGUGUUAUUCUGAAGCCCUCUUCUUAAAAAGGUUCUAUUUCUUGUUAUUUAUUUAGAUAUACUUUUAUUUCUGUUUUAACUUUCUAAGUGAUUACUGUUAAUCAUUUUCAUAUAUGGUUUUCUAUAGUCAAAUAAUCUUAUUGAGUAUUUUUUUCCCUAUCAUUUCAGGUUUUGAGUUUGCCAUCAUGUCAUUAACUGCAAAUAGUUGAUCUCCUUAUAAUUUUAUGCCUCUUUUUGUUAGCCUUGGCUUAUCUCAAUAACCAUUAUUUCUACACAUUGCUGAGUUACAGGGAUAAGAGUUGGUGUCCUUGUUCUUUUUUCUUUCCUGGGAAUUGUUCUAGUACUGAGAUUUCCUCUUUGGCUUGAAGUUUCUGGUCUUCACUCUAGCACUAAUUGAAAAAAAAAAAAUUUGUUUUCCGAGAACUGUUACUUUCCUCCAUAUUUUCAAAUUUAUUAACAGAGAAUUGUACAGAGUGAUUUAUUUUACAACAAUAAAAUUCUAUUUGUGAGUACUUUGUUUUGAAAAGUUCAGAUCAACUGAUAAUACUAGUGCUGUGAUGAGACUCAGCUUGUACUCAAGAACAGAUUUAUGACUAGCUUAUAGUUGGCUGCUUCACCAGGACUCUACAAAUUGCUCAGAACCCAAGGAGAGAGAAACUAGUCAUUCGACAAAGAUUGAACUUCUUCUGUGUGUUAGGCUGUGCUCCAAGUGCUGGGAAGACACCAGUGAAUAAAACAAAAAGUCCCUGCUCUCAUGGAGUUUACAGCCACUAUUCUAAAACCUAGAGGAUCAAGACAUAAUGGGAGCAUUUUUAGACAAGCCAAAGAUGGAAAAGCAUAAUGCCCAGGGGCAGGGUAAUGGGUUGCGAUAUGGGCUAAGCAGCAUGCAAGGCUGGCGUGUUGAAAUGGAGGAUGCACAUACGGCUGUGAUCGGUUUGCCAAGUGGACUUGAAUCGUGGUCAUUCUUUGCUGUGUAUGAUGGGCAUGCUGGUUCUCAGGUUGCCAAAUACUGCUGUGAGCAUUUGUUAGAUCACAUCACCAAUAACCAGGAUUUUAAAGGGUCUGCAGGAGCACCUUCUGUGGAAAAUGUAAAGAAUGGAAUCAGAACAGGUUUUCUGGAGAUUGAUGAACACAUGAGAGUUAUGUCAGAGAAGAAACAUGGUGCAGAUAGAAGUGGGUCAACAGCUGUAGGUGUCUUAAUUUCUCCCCAACAUACUUAUUUCAUUAACUGUGGAGACUCAAGAGGUUUACUUUGUAGGAACAGGAAAGUUCAUUUCUUCACACAAGAUCACAAACCAAGUAAUCCGCUGGAGAAAGAACGAAUUCAGAAUGCAGGUGGCUCUGUAAUGAUUCAGCGUGUGAAUGGCUCUCUGGCUGUAUCGAGGGCCCUUGGGGAUUUUGAUUACAAAUGUGUCCAUGGAAAAGGUCCUACUGAGCAGCUUGUCUCACCAGAGCCUGAAGUCCAUGAUAUUGAAAGAUCUGAAGAAGAUGAUCAGUUCAUUAUCCUUGCAUGUGAUGGUAUCUGGGAUGUUAUGGGAAAUGAAGAGCUCUGUGAUUUUGUAAGAUCCAGACUUGAAGUCACUGAUGACCUUGAGAAAGUUUGCAAUGAAGUAGUCGACACCUGUUUGUAUAAGGGAAGUCGAGACAACAUGAGUGUGAUUUUGAUCUGUUUUCCAAAUGCACCCAAAGUAUCGCCAGAAGCAGUGAAGAAGGAGGCAGAGUUGGACAAGUACCUGGAAUGCAGAGUAGAAGAAAUCAUAAAGAAGCAGGGGGAAGGCGUCCCCGACUUAGUCCAUGUGAUGCGCACAUUAGCGAGUGAGAACAUCCCCAGCCUCCCACCAGGGGGUGAAUUGGCAAGCAAGAGGAAUGUUAUUGAAGCCGUUUACAAUAGACUGAAUCCUUACAAAAAUGACGACACUGACUCUACAUCAACAGAUGAUAUGUGGUAAAACUGCUCAUCUAGCCAUGGAGUUUACCUUCACCUCCAAAGGAGAGUACAGCUCAACUUUGUUGAAACUUUUAACAUCCAUCCUCAACUUUAAGGAAGGGGAUAUGACAUGGGUGAGAAUGAUUACAUCAGAGAACUUCAGCAGUACAACAGCUAGCCCAGAACUGAUUUUUUUUUUUUUUUUUGUAAAUUUGAGACUUAUGUAAGCGUGAUUUCAAACCAUAAUUCGUGUUGUAAAUCAGACUCCAGCAAUUUUUGUUGUAUGAUUUUGUUUUUUUGUAAAGUGUAAUUGUCCUUGUACAAAAUGCUCAUAUUUAAUUAUGAACUGCUUUAAAUCACUAUCAAAGUUACAAGAAAUGUUUGGCUUAUUGUGUGAUGCAACAGAUAUAUAGCCCUUUCAAGUCAUGUUGUGUUUGGACUUGGGGUUGGAACAGGGAGAGCAGCAGCCAUGUCAGCUACACGCUCAAAUGUGCAGAUGAUUAUGGAAAAUAACCUCAAAAUCUUACAAAGCUGAACAUCCAAGGAGUUAUUGAAAACUAUCUUAAAUGUUCUUGGUAGGGGAGUUGGCAUUGUUGAUAAAGCCAGUCCCUUCAUUUAACUGUCUUUCAGGAUGUUCCUUCGUUGUUUCCAUGAGUAUUGCAGGUAAUAAUACAGUGUAUUCAUAAGAAUCUCAAUCUUGGGGCUAAAUGCCUUGUUUCUUUGCACCUCUUUUCAAGUCCUUACAUUUAAUUACUAAUUGAUAAGCAGCAGCUUCCUACAUAUAGUAGGAAACUGCCACAUUUUUGCUAUCAUGAUUGGCUGGGCCUGCUGCUGUUCCUAGUAAGAUAUUCUGAAUUCCAUUUUAUCAAUAAAGCUUGAUUUAACAAACAAGAAACUUAAUCAUGUAUGUGUAAUUCCUCUUUUACCCUGGCCUUUUAAAACACUGUGCCGUUGUAAUGAGACGUUUCUCAUAGGGAAAGAUGUUAGUCUCUUUUAAUUGGACAACACUGUCACUCAAGGCAUAGAUGAAACUUUCCUUCCAUUAGAAAGACUAAAAGAUUUAAUUCUUGGUUGUACCUUAAUCUAUUUUUUAAAUAGGUUUCUUUCAGGCUGCUUAUUUUUCAUUAAGAUGUGUAUCAGCUUGGAUUUGCCUACUGUUUAAUUAAAAUAUUUAUUGUCAAAGUUUGACAAUCUAACACUCUAUGGUAGGGGUGUGUGUGUGUGUGUUUGUGAGUGUGUGUUUGCCUGUGAUUUUUAAUUGGCCCAUGUCUUUAGAAUCCAAGUGGUUAAGAUGUAUUUGUGAUUUGAAAUAUAGCAUGUUGAUAAUAUUUAGCUGUUGGCCUUUACAAAUAACUUUCAAAGCUUAAGGAAUUGUAGAUAUAAAAAUAACCUAAUUUAAUUUAGGCUUAAAUUCCUCUGAUUAAGCAUGUGAAAGUAAGUUUUAAAAUCUGUCGCAUUGAAAAGAUUACUGUUCCGUGCCCUUCUGUAUUUUUGUCUCUUUAGGUUGAAUAUUGUAUUUAUCACCAUGUAAUCAUUCAGUAGGCAGAUUCCCACUAGAAAACUGUUGAAAUGUAAGACUAAAAUACAACAUUGAAUACAAAAUCAAAAUUUUGUGUAUAAAAACCAGUAUAGUCCAUUUUGUUAUAUUUGUUUUUUCCCUAACUUGGAAAUAUACAUAUUUGUAUAUAUAGCCUUAAAAUUAAUGUAAAGUUAGGGGAGUAGUGGGGAAAGUAAUGUGAAAUGUCUCAGAUUUAAGUAGUUAAAUACCAGCAAAAUCUUUUCAUUAUCCCUCUUAUUUUGUGAGGUGAUUAAAUGUAACUUAAUUGUAUUUAAUUUAUAUCUUAUUCCAGCAUGAAUGAGGAAAAACUGAAGUACUAUUUAUAUUUAGAAAUUCAUAUCAGUUGAAAUUACAGAACCAAUUCCAUACUUACAAUAAAUACUUAAUGUCUAAAUCUGUGGUAGAGUGCGAAGUAUGAUAAUGUUCUAAGUUAUGGCUUUGCAAGCAUCUAAAUGUGCAUUUAAUGAAUACCAGUGCUUCUAGUAUAGACUAAUUACCAGACAUACUGGUACUGAAAGCUAAAUCCCUAUUAUAACAAACCAGUUCCUUAAUAUUUUAAGUAGACUGACAACUUUAGUUCCAGAAAUUGCAAAACUUUGAACUGGACUGUGUAAUCUUUUGAGAUGCAAAACUUAAGUCACAAGUAGAGUAUGUGAUGGAAAGCUGUAUUUCAAACCAUAACAGCAUAUUUAGAGCCUUUUUUUUUUGAGUCUUUAAACAAGAGAAAAUUAAAAUAUUCCUGUCAAAAUUAUUAGUAUUGAAAUUAGGCUUGGACACGAGAGAGAACCGUAUUUGAGUGAUGUGAGAAGACUAAAUCUUUUCCACAUGAGUCAGCACUGCCAUACUAAUAAUUUUUUUACUAUAAAAAUACAGGAAGGAAGUAUACAUUAUAACAGCAGACUGUGUGUGUUCCUGAUUCCUGGAGGUAAUAGUGGGGGGAAACCAACCAUACUUUUUAAAGGCACUUUUGCACCUCUAUUGUGCACUUCAUUCUUGUACCACUUAAAUUCUUCACCCCCAUCCCCUUUUUUUGUGCUAAUUAGCAUCUCAGGGCAAUGCCUCAAAAAUGUUUGAUGUGUUCUGUUCUUUGGAGGGAAAAAGUUCUUAUGUGAUGAUAAUAUAGUACUCAAAAUAUACUUUUAUCAUUUAAAUGUCUUAUUUGCUGCUAUGAAUAGGAAAUAACAUUUUGUAUAGCAGGCUCUGUUUUACCCUAACAUUAAAAAAUUUCACUGAUCUUUCUUUCAUUAACAGGGUAGAAUCUCCUAAUUUCCACUUUCUUGGGAAUAUACUUUUAUAGACAAUAGAAGCAGUUCUCAAUAUUAGCAUAUACUUUAAAAAAUCAAAGUGAUAACUUAAUUCAGCUUUGGAAGUAUCUCAAACAUAUUUUUACUUUAUAGUGCAUUAACUUGCUUCUAGAGUACUUAAUGCAACUGCUCUAGCCACUUAAUUUUUUAUACUAAUCUCAACAUUAAGAAAUUUGGAUUAAGUAAUAAAUUAGUUAUGUAAUUCAAGUAAUCUGAAUUACAGCAGUACUUUUAGUGAUCAUUCAUAGGACUAUAUAUUAACCCAGCUAAUAACUCAGUUUUUUUACAAAAUGUUUCGAGUAUUAUUGGUAAAACACUGUUCUAGGCUAAGCACAUUGGGACUGUAAAGAAAUGAGUAGAUCCUUGGCUUCAAGUUUACAUCUGGACAAUUUAUAAUCUAGUGUAUGUUAGUAUUAUAACUGGAUCACUCAUCAAAAAAUAUAUAUAUAUAUCUAUUGCCCACCUGCUAUCUACCAGGUACUUAGCUGAUCAAGGCAGGCCCCUGCCCUAAAGACCUUGUUUAUACUUCCUUUACUCACCUGAAAACUGUUCUCCAGUUUAUUUUCUUCUCUCUAAAGUUAAAGAGUAAUUCAGAAGAAAAUUUUGCUUAGCAUAAGAAUAAAAUUGGACUGAAGAGGCUUAAGCCCAUUCAGUAUCCUUGAUUGCAUUUAUCCAACGGCCUUUAUUCUUCCUGCUGACAGCAGUAACUCAGAGGAAUAGGUAGUAGAUUUCUGAAAAUUAUCCAGCCAUGGAAAUGUAGGUGGGGUUUGAGUUUAAGGCAUUUAAAAAUGUAAAUAUCUCUAGCUAAAUUUAUCUUAAGUAGAACUCUGUGUUUUUGUAACACACUGCCAGUGUUAAUAUCAAAUUUUAGCCAAAUUAUUACUAUGUGUUUUAAUAUUUUAAAAUAAUUUCACUGCCCAUCUUUACUGGACAAACUCAUUUGGAGUUCAACUUGUGAUUUCUGAAAGAACUGAUGAAAUUGGGUACUGCUUUUUUUCUCCAUUUUUCGUUUUGUUUUAAUUUUGAAUUUCAUGGUAUAUACUUUUAGUUCAAACUCAGCUGUUUGUACAGUAUUGUAUUAGGAUUUGGUAUUAGAAAAGAUGUGUAAAUAUCUUAGUAUAUAAUUGUUUCUCAUUUGAGGUUUUUCUUCUAAGGGACCUUAAAGAGUUUUAUAUACUUUUGCUCACAGAAACUGCUGGUGAGAUUACCAUUUUUUGAGUAUCUAGUCUUCUAGUUUUUCUUUUAGGCAUUAGGAAGCCUUCUUUAGAGUUCAAAAUUUUAGAAGCCUAAUUUGCUCUUACUUCCUUCAAUUAUGUGCCAUGUGUUUUGGUUUGUAUAUGUUUUAAAUUGUAUAUUUCCUUGGAAUAUGCUUGAAAUAUUUAAGAAUACAUUUUCAAAAUGUAUAAUACUGUAUUGUUUUGUUGAUCAGAAUAAUAAGUCUCAGUUAAAUGUUUGUUAUUACUGAUAGUCAAAAUGCUCAAUAGAAAUGAUGAGAGGCAUUGGUUCCAAUUCAUUGUCAAAUGAACGUUUUCUAAUUUUGUUCACAGAUUCUUUCCCUUUCGAUUGUUCUGUAUGUUAAGAUAGUGGCUUCUGCUCUCACUGUUUUCCUAUUUAUAUUACUAGCAGGUAGGAGUGCUAAUUAGAAAAACUUAGAUGGUAUUGAAAUUACAGUUGACAACUUAUAUUUUUAUGAGAUGGAGAAAAAAGAUUAAGUUGAUAUAACAACAAAGUGGACUUUUUUUCUUCCUUAUCCUGCACGAAAUAUUGCCCUUGUUUCCUCUACUUUCCUCUUGGUGUUUUCUCUUUUUUUCAAACAGAAACAGGCCAAUUCCAUUUUCUUGAGCAAGAAAGCUUAGUGUGUUACUUCAUCAAGGCCAGCUAAUACUGUGUUAAACCGGGCUGAAAAUGAGAAAACUUGGGAGAUGGAGGAAUGGGGAAAUGGCAGUGGGAUAGGUAGGGAAGGAUUACUCUUAAUUGUUUUAAAAGCCAUAGGAAAGUCUUCCUUGUACGUGGCUGUAAAUUUAUAAGAACUAUUGUGUCACAUAAACCAACAAGAAUGAACCUUUGCUGCUUCAGAUAAUUUGAUUUUUCCAGCAAGGAAAUUAAUAAGUUACUGAUUCUUCAGCAUAGAAACAACUGAGAAGAAUUAAUGCAAUGUUUCUUCACUAGAAAACCCAACCCUUCAUUUCUUUUCAUUGCUCCAAAACCCAGUUUUCAACUAAUGGUUUUCUCAUUAAACUAAAUGUUUAGAAAAGUUGUUUAGAGUUUUUCUUUUUCUUUUACAUAGUCCUCCUGAUCCAGUAUAAGACUAUUUAGUAACGUGCAUUUGUAUGGUACUAUCUAAAGUAAGUUAGAUUGAUGUAAGAGAUCGGGUAGCUGCGGAACAAAAUUAGUUAUAUCCUAAUUAGGUACAGUGAAUGACACAAAAUCAUUUUAGCAAUGCUUCUUAACCUUUUGGGGUCACAGGCGUUUUGAGACUGAUGAAUCCUAGGGACUUAUUUACCCAGGAAAAUGCGUAUAUAACAUACAUAUCUCCCUAAAGUUUACAAUAUUGUAGUGGUUCAUGGGCCCCCUGGUUAAGAGCCCAUUCUAAAGUACAAUAGGGCAUCAUCCCUUUUCCUGCAAAGCCCAAAAGUAUAUUUCUAGGGCAUGAAAAUAACUUGAGUCUAUUUUAAGGAAUUGUUUCACUCUAGAGGUAGAUAGGGGACCUGGCUAGAAUCUGACAUUAAAAUAUACUUUUUAAAAAAUAUUAUAUUUGGGGUGGGGAAAGUGAUUAAAAGGUGAAAAAAAAACAUAGUAUUCAGAAGUUUUGGAGGUUAAUGUCUUUCUCUAAGAUUUGCCACUUUAGAAAUUCAACAGAAAAGAGGUAAAACAGAAAUGGAAUGUAUCUGGAACAUUUUUGGCCUCCAUAGUGCAGAUAUACUAUAUUAACAAGUAAUACAUUUAUUUACCUGUCAGAUCUCCAGGUUUUAAGAUUUUGAGCUUUCUAGUAUUAGGAUUCAUUAAAUGUUCAAUUCAUUUCAUAUUCUAAGGAAUUAGGUUAUUUACUUACUAAUUCAGGAUGUUAAAAUAACAUCCAAGUCGGACAACCACCACCAAUGCACACAGUUAAUGAGAUUUCUAAAAUAUAAUAAGUACAAUGUAACAAACGUAUAGAAUUUUGCAUUUGUUGCCAAAAUUAGAUGUUUAAUGACAGCUUAUUUAAUUCCCAUUUGUGGGACUUCUGGAACAUAGAAACCAUUAUCUUACCUGGUUAUCCCUUGACUAAAUAGCAUAUCUGCAGGAAAAUAUCUUGUUUGUAGUGAUAUGCCCCAAUAGUGAUUGAUUUCACUCUUGAAAUGAGUUAUAUCACUUAAUUUGUAUAAAUGUUAUGAGUGGAGAGACAUGUACAUGUUAAAAGCAUGUUGCAUUAUAUAUUCAUUUUUUAAACUCUAUAAAUGUUAAGAAUAAUAUAAUUGCAGAAAUAUUUUUCUUAAAUACAAUGUGUAACAAAAUUCUCCGUAGCAACUCACCCACUUUGCAGUUUAUGUGAUCCACACUUUUAAAGAAAUUCCAUAAAUGUAUAUUUUGUAUUAUGUAUUAUUUCCUGGUCCAAAGAAAAUAUGUGAAUUCAGUUCUAACUUUAAGAAUGUACUGUUUGUUUUCAAGUUCAUUGAAAAAUUGCAUUCAGCCUGCGAAUGGUUGCAGAUUGUAUGUUAGAUGAAAAGUAGAAAUAAUUUCUAGUUUGGAAAACUGGUGCCACUAAAUAAACAGGCAAUUACAUAA